AUAUCAUCAUUAGGCGUCAACACAGGAAGUGAGGAUACUUCUGGCGAGCGCCGGUUGCUGUUUCUUCUCAGGCUCAGGGACCGGCCGCGGCCCCGUAGGGUGUUUUAACUCAAAUGGGUGAUGAAAAGGACUCUUGGAAAGUGAAAACUUUAGAUGAAAUUCUUCAGGAAAAGAAACGAAGGAAGGAACAAGAGGAGAAAGCAGAGAUAAAACGCUUAAAAAAUUCUGAUGACCGGGAUUCCAAGCGGGAUUCCCUUGAGGAGGGGGAGCUGAGAGAUCACUGCAUGGAGAUCACAAUAAGGAACUCCCCGUAUAGAAGAGAAGACUCAAUGGAAGACAGAGGAGAAGAAGAUGAUUCUUUGGCCAUCAAACCACCCCAGCAAAUGUCUCGGAAAGAAAAAGUUCAUCACAGAAAAGAUGAAAAGAGAAAAGAAAAAUGGAAGCAUGCUAGAGUGAAAGAAAGAGAGCACGAACGUCGGAAACGACAUCGAGAAGAACAGGAUAAAGCUCGCCGGGAAUGGGAAAGACAGAAGAGAAGGGAAAUGGCAAGGGAGCAUUCCAGGAGAGAAAGGGACCGCUUGGAGCAGUUAGAAAGGAAGCGGGAGCGGGAGCGCAAGAUGCGGGAGCAGCAGAAGGAGCAGCGGGAGCAGAAGGAGCGCGAGCGGCGGGCGGAGGAGCGGCGCAAGGAGCGGGAGGCCCGCAGGGAAGUGUCUGCACAUCACCGAACGAUGAGAGAGGACUACAGCGACAAAGUGAAAGCCAGCCACUGGAGUCGCAGCCCGCCUCGGCCGCCGCGGGAGCGGUUCGAGUUGGGAGACGGCCGGAAGCCAGGUGAGGCCAGGCCGGCGCCUGCGCAGAAGCCAGCACAGUUAAAAGAAGAGAAAAUGGAAGAAAGGGACCUGCUGUCCGACUUACAGGACAUCAGCGACAGCGAGAGGAAGACCAGCUCGGCCGAGUCCUCGUCAGCGGAAUCAGGCUCAGGUUCUGAGGAAGAAGAGGAGGAGGAGGAAGAGGAGGAGGAGGAAGGGAGCACCAGUGAAGAAUCAGAGGAGGAGGAGGAGGAAGAGGAAGAGGAGGAGGAGGAGACCGGCAGCAACUCUGAGGAGGCAUCAGAGCAGUCUGCCGAAGAAGUAAGUGAGGAAGAAAUGAGUGAAGAUGAAGAACGAGAAAAUGAAAACCACCUCUUGGUUGUUCCAGAGUCACGGUUCGACCGAGAUUCCGGGGAGAGUGAAGAAGCAGAGGAAGAAGUGGGUGAGGGAACGCCGCAGAGCAGCGCCCUGACAGAGGGCGACUAUGUGCCCGACUCCCCUGCCCUGUUGCCCAUCGAGCUCAAGCAGGAGCUGCCCAAGUACCUGCCGGCCCUGCAGGGCUGCCGGAGCGUCGAGGAGUUCCAGUGCCUGAACAGGAUCGAGGAGGGCACCUAUGGAGUGGUCUACAGAGCAAAAGACAAGAAAACAGAUGAAAUUGUGGCUCUAAAGCGGCUGAAGAUGGAGAAGGAGAAGGAGGGCUUCCCGAUCACGUCCCUGAGGGAGAUCAACACCAUCCUCAAGGCCCAGCAUCCCAACAUUGUCACCGUUAGAGAGAUUGUGGUGGGCAGCAACAUGGACAAGAUCUACAUCGUGAUGAACUACGUGGAGCACGACCUCAAGAGCCUGAUGGAGACCAUGAAACAGCCCUUCCUGCCAGGGGAGGUGAAGACCCUGAUGAUCCAGCUGCUGCGGGGGGUGAAACACCUGCACGACAACUGGAUCCUGCACCGUGACCUCAAGACGUCCAACCUGCUGCUGAGCCACGCCGGCAUCCUCAAGGUGGGUGAUUUUGGGCUGGCGCGGGAGUACGGAUCCCCUCUGAAGGCCUACACCCCGGUCGUGGUGACCCAGUGGUACCGCGCCCCAGAGCUGCUGCUUGGUGCCAAGGAAUACUCCACGGCCGUGGACAUGUGGUCAGUGGGCUGCAUCUUCGGGGAGCUGCUGACUCAGAAGCCUCUGUUCCCCGGGAAUUCGGAAAUCGAUCAGAUCAACAAAGUGUUCAAGGAGCUGGGGACCCCCAGUGAGAAAAUCUGGCCCGGCUACAGUGAGCUCCCAGUAGUCAAAAAGAUGACCUUCAGCGAGCACCCCUACAACAACCUCCGCAAGCGCUUCGGGGCUCUGCUCUCAGACCAGGGCUUCGACCUCAUGAACAAGUUCCUGACCUACUUCCCCGGGAGGAGGAUCAGCGCUGAGGACGGCCUCAAGCAUGAGUAUUUCCGCGAGACCCCCCUCCCCAUCGACCCCUCCAUGUUCCCCACGUGGCCCGCCAAGAGCGAGCAGCAGCGUGUGAAGCGGGGCACCAGCCCGAGGCCCCCUGAGGGAGGCCUGGGCUACAGCCAGCUGGGUGACGACGACCUGAAGGAGACGGGCUUCCACCUUACCACCACGAACCAGGGGGCCUCUGCCGCGGGCCCCGGCUUCAGCCUCAAGUUCUGAAGGUCAGAGUGGACCCCGUCAUGGGGAGAACUCAGCCGGGACCACAGGCGUGGCUACUGCGGCUGGAGCUGCGAUGAGACUCGGAACUCCUCGUCUUACUUUGUGCUCCAUGUUUUGUUUUUGUAUUUUGGUUUGUAAAUUUGUAGAAUUAAAUCAUUUUCCUUGUUGUGGAGGAAAGAGCUGUGUUUUCUCCGUGACUUGCCAGGGCAUCUUCGGGUGCCCACGUGGGGCAGCACAAACCUCCACACACCCUCUCCCACUCUCGACACGCACGGGGCUGGCUGGGCCGUGAUUUGGAAAGGAACUGGUGGGAGCCGGGUGGAUUGUUUAAUCUUCGGAGCUGGAGACCUGUUUCUGUGUUGGGAUGAGCGAUGCCCUCUUGCCCCAACCCACUCGUCCAGACCAGCCCUGUCCACACAGGCCCCCGGCCCCCAACCCCCAGCCCCAGCUGUGCCAGCAGACUCGACAGGUUUUUAUACAAGGUUGUUGAGUUUUAAAAUGUAUUAAAAUAUUCUUCGAGGAAAGCUC